GAGUGCCAGGCUGGGCCACGAGACACAGGACACAAUUUCUUGCCAGGGUCCUGGUAGCUUCCUCUUCAACAGCCACUUCCGUGUGGCCGGGGCCCCAGGGGCAGGAGCUGCUGCCCGUUGCCCAGGCCACCCUCCACCCCCAAUUGGGAGCCCUGCCCCCCUGGGGCCGGGCCAAGCCCAGCAGCUGGCUGGGAUCCCAUGGGGGACUGGUAGGGCACAGGUCUUGGGGGAUAGAGGUGACCGGGCCAGUGCCCUGGGGCUCUGGCCAUGAAGUCUCGGCAGAAAGGAAAGAAGAAGGGCAGCGCAAAGGAGCGGGUUUUUGGGUGCGACUUGCAGGAGCACCUGCAGCACUCAGGCCAGGAGGUGCCCCAGGUGCUAAAGAGCUGUGCAGAAUUUGUGGAGGAGUAUGGAGUGGUGGAUGGGAUCUACCGCCUCUCAGGGGUCUCCUCCAACAUCCAGAAGCUUCGGCAGGAAUUUGAGUCAGAGCGGAAGCCAGACCUGCGUCGGGAUGUUUACCUCCAAGACAUUCACUGCGUCUCCUCCCUGUGCAAGGCCUAUUUCAGAGAACUGCCGGAUCCCCUGCUCACUUACCGGCUCUAUGACAAGUUUGCUGAGGCUGUAGGAGUGCAAUUGGAACCUGAGCGCUUGGUCAAGAUCCUAGAGGUGCUUCGGGAACUCCCUGUCCCAAACUACAGGACCCUGGAGUUCCUCAUGAGGCACUUGGUACACAUGGCCUCAUUCAGUGCCCAGACCAACAUGCAUGCUCGCAACCUGGCCAUCGUGUGGGCUCCCAACCUGCUGAGGUCUAAGGACAUAGAGGCCUCAGGCUUCAAUGGGACAGCGGCCUUCAUGGAGGUGCGGGUACAAUCCAUCGUCGUGGAGUUCAUCCUCACACACGUGGACCAGCUCUUUGGGGGUGCUGCCCUCUCUGGUGGUGAGGUGGAGAGUGGGUGGCGAUCGCUUCCAGGGACCCGGGCAUCAGGCAGCCCCGAGGACCUUAUGCCCAGGCCACUGCCUUAUCACCUGCCUAGCAUACUGCAGGCUGGCGAUGGACCCCCACAGAUGCGGCCCUACCAUACUAUCAUCGAGAUUGCAGAGCACAAGAGGAAGGGGUCUUUGAAGGUCAGGAAGUGGAGGUCUAUCUUCAAUUUAGGUCGCUCUGGCCAUGAGACUAAGCGUAAACUUCCACGGGGGGCUGAGGACAGGGAGGAUAAAUCCAACAAGGGGACACUGCGGCCAGCCAAAAGCAUGGACUCACUGAGUGCUGCAGCUGGGGCCAGUGAUGAGCCAGAGGGGCUGGUGGGGCCCAGCAGCCCCCGGCCAAGCCCAUUGCUGCCUGAGAGCUUGGAGAACGAUUCUAUAGAGGCAGCAGAGGGUGAACAGGAGCCUGAGGCAGAAGCACUGGGUGGCACAAACUCUGAACCAGGCACACCACGAGCUGGGCGGUCAGCCAUCCGGGCUGGGGGCAGCAGCCGUGCAGAACGCUGUGCUGGUGUCCACAUCUCAGACCCCUACAAUGUCAACCUCCCGCUACACAUCACCUCUAUCCUCAGUGUGCCCCCGAACAUCAUCUCUAACGUUUCCUUGGCCAGGCUCACCCGUGGCCUUGAGUGCCCUGCUCUACAGCACCGGCCAAGCCCUGCCUCUGGCCCUGGCCCUGGCCCUGGCCUUGGCCCUGGCCCCCCAGAUGAAAAGUUGGAAGCAAGUCCAGCCUCAAGUCCCCUGGCAGACUCAGGCCCAGACGACUUGGCUCCUGCCCUGGAGGACUCGCUGUCCCAGGAGGUGCAGGACUCCUUCUCCUUCCUAGAGGACUCAAGCAGCUCAGAACCUGAGUGGGUGGGGGCAGAGGAUGGGGAGGUGGCCCAGGCAGAAGCAGCAGGAGCAGCCUUCUCCCCUGGGGAGGACGACCCUGGGAUGGGCUACCUGGAGGAGCUCCUGGGAGUUGGGCCUCAGGUGGAGGAGUUCUCUGUGGAGCCACCCCUGGAUGACCUGUCUCUGGAUGAGGCACAGUUUGUCUUGGCCCCCAGCUGCUGUUCCCUGGACUCCGCUGGCCCCAGGCCUGAAGUUGAGGAGGAAAAUGGGGAGGAAGUUUUCCUGAGUGCCUAUGAUGACCUAAGUCCCCUUCUGGGACCUAAACCCCCAAUCUGGAAGGGUUCAGGGAGUCUGGAGGGAGAGGCAGCAGGAUGUGGAAGGCAGGCUCUGGGACAGGGUGGGGAAGAGCAGGCAUGCUGGGAAGUUGGGGAGGACAAGCAGGCUGAGCCUGGAGGCAGGCUAGACAUCAGGGAAGAGGCAGAGGGAAGUCCAGAGACCAAGGUGGAGGCUGGAAAGGCCAGUGAGGAUAGAGGGGAGGCUGGGGGAAGCCAAGAGACAAAAGUCAGAUUGAGAGAAGGGAGUAGGGAAGAGACAGAGGCCAAGGAAGAGAAGUCCAAAGGUCAGAAGAAGGCUGACAGUAUGGAGGCUAAAGGUGUGGAGGAACCAGGAGGAGAUGAGUAUACAGAUGAGAAGGAAAAAGAAAUUGAGAGAGAAGAGGAUGAACAAAGAGAGGAAGCCCAGGUAGAAGCUGGAAGGGACCUAGAGCAAGGGGCCCAGGAAGAUCAAGUUGCUGAGGAGAAAUGGGAAGUUGUACAGAAACAAGAGGCUGAGGGAGUCAGAGAGGAUGAGGACAAAGGACAGAGGGAGAAGGGGUACCAUGAAGCAAGAAAAGACCAAGGAGAUGGUGAAGACAGCAGAAGCCCAGAAGCAGCAACUGAAGGAGGAGCAGGGGAGGUCAGCAAGGAACGGGAGAGUGGGGAUGGAGAGGCUGAGGGAGACCAGAGGGCUGGAGGGUACUAUUUAGAAGAGGACACCCUCUCUGAAGGUUCAGGUGUAGCGUCCCUGGAGGUUGACUGUGCCAAAGAGGGCAAUCCUCACUCUUCUGAGAUGGAAGAGGUAGCCCCACAGCCACCUCAGCCAGAGGAGAUGGAGCCUGAGGGGCAGCCCAGUCCAGACGGCUGUCUAUGCCCCUGUUCUCUUGGCCUGGGUGGCGUGGGCAUGCGUCUAGCUUCCACUCUGGUUCAGGUCCAACAGGUCCGCUCUGUGCCUGUGGUGCCCCCCAAGCCACAGUUUGCCAAGAUGCCCAGUGCAAUGUGUAGCAAGAUUCAUGUGGCACCUGCAAAUCCAUGCCCGAGGCCUGGCCGGCUUGAUGGGACUCCUGGAGAAAGGGCUUGGGGGUCCCGAGCUUCUCGAUCCUCUUGGAGGAAUGGGGGUAGUCUUUCCUUUGAUGCUGCUGUGGCCCUAGCCCGGGACCGCCAAAGGACUGAGGCUCAAGGAGUUCGGCGAACCCAGACCUGUACUGAGGGUGGGGAUUACUGCCUCAUCCCCAGAACCUCCCCUUGUAGCAUGAUCUCUGCCCAUUCUCCUCGGCCCCUUAGCUGCCUGGAGCUCCCAUCUGAAGGUGCAGAAGGGUCUGGAUCCCGGAGUCGUCUUAGUCUGCCCCCCAGAGAACCCCAGGUUCCUGACCCCCUGUUGUCCUCUCAGCGCAGGUCAUAUGCAUUUGAAACACAGGCUAACCCUGGGAAAGGUGAAGGACUGUGAUUAGGACCACAGCCCUGGGCAAAGGGGACCAGCAAGUUGUCUUGAAUCUCCAGGGUUCCUGACUAGCUGUCUCCUCUGCAGCAUGAGCAGCUGUAGUGCCCAACUCUAUAGGCUUUGGCCCUCCAGCUUCUCUCUUUGACUGUGGGAGGCACUGCCUUGGUUGGUUUACCUGAACUUGUCUCCGACACAAAGCACUUAUCUCUUAGGAGAUUCCCAAGAAAGUCAACAAGAUCUUGUUCCCAGGGAGUGGGUCAUUGGCCAAAGGGAACAUAAGGUAGGCAGAAAACUUAAAAGAGUUUGUUAAAGUGAAGACUGGAGAAAUUCCUCCCUUCCUCUGAGCUGUGAAUCUCUCUUCAUGAAAGCCAAAGGUAGAGACAGGGAGGACAGGGCCAGGUUAGGGCCUUCCACACACAAACACUUCUAGAGUUGCCCAUUCCUGUUAUGUUCUUGGACCCUAAGAUACCUCCUGUCCCUUUUAAAUCCAGAUUAAGAGAAACGUCCAGGAAGAGCUCUUUGAAGCCCUCAAUAUUUGUUGGAGGGACUGGACUCCUCUCCAGCUCCCCACCCUCUGCCUCCAGUCACCAUGUGCAAGAGAGGUCCUGUACAGAUCUCUCUGGGCUCUCCUUUCUCCUUUGGAAUAACUUGUUCCUAUUUCAGGAAAGGGAAAUGGUGUCACUCAGGCCCUGGGACUGCUUCUCCAGCCAGGCUGGGGCCACAGGUCCCACUCUAGUGAAGGUCAAUGUCUCAGAAUAAAAGCUGUAUUUUUACA